ACACAGUAUUCUGAACUCCUGGAUCUACCACCUCCUGCUUCCCAAGGACCAUGAAACUCCUGCUGCUGGCUCUUCCUAUGCUUGUGCUCCUACCCCAAGUGAUCCCAGCCUAUAGUGGUGAAAAAAAAUGCUGGAACAGAUCAGGGCACUGCAGGAAACAAUGCAAAGAUGGAGAAGCAGUGAAAGAUACAUGCAAAAAUCUUCGAGCUUGCUGCAUUCCAUCCAAUGAAGACCACAGGCGAGUUCCUGCGACAUCUCCCACACCCUUGAGUGACUCAACACCAGGAAUUAUUGAUGAUAUUUUAACAGUAAGGUUCACGACAGACUACUUUGAAGUAAGCAGCAAGAAAGAUAUGGUUGAAGAGUCUGAGGCGGGAAGGGGAACUGAGACCUCUCUUCCAAAUGUUCACCAUAGCUCAUGACUUCCUCUCGGCUAUCACUCACCCCUGUCCUCAGAGUGAUAAACUAAGUCACAUACAGAUAAAGCACUGAAAACACCACAGUGACCCUCCCACCCCCCACCAAUAUGUAAUUCUAUUAAUAGAAACAGCUGUGUAAAGAAGUCUAAAAUUUUCACUAUUUCCAAUGAUAAACUCUUCAGUGCUCUUCUUGAAAUGUCACAUUAUUUCCACAACAAGUUAUAACCUAUUUUUAGUAUUUCUUGUUUGCUAGUGACCUAUGCACAACUUCAAUAGCUUAGUUAGCUAUUCCAACAACAAUUUCUUCAUGUAUCGUUCUGUCUUCUCAACAGCUGUCUUCAUGGCAGCAUAAGUGGUCAUGAUCAAAAUUCUAAAUCUUUGCAUCUGUGAGAGUAGCUACUAUGACACUAAAAGCUUUUUUUCUAGAACAGGAGACACUUCAGGUGAAAGCAUUCAUUCUCCUACUAACUAUGGCCUUGGAGCCAGGUUUUAUCUCUCACUGUAGGAAAUUGGCCGCCCCAGGUGUGAGCUAUGAAGACUCCUUUUUGCCCCAGUGGCUUUGGGGUUGAAAUGCUGUCGAAAAGCUUUUAUGGCUCUGUAGACCCAUCUUUUUGACCAAGCCUUGAUCACACAUGGACAUCCAAGGGUAAUCAUGGACCCCCAAUUGUGGGUGAAAGGAUGGAUCAUUUAUCUACCUGAUUACUGAGAGCUUUAUUUGUCUCCCUCUGAUAGCAAAAAAAAAAAAAAAAAAAAAAA